UGGGCGUUUGGUAACCGGCAUGGCUGCUACCUGUUUCUGGCUGGAGCCUCGGACACUGGCUCACUGCAGUUGGUGGUGUCCACAGAGCGGUAGGAGGGCAACUAGUAGCGGGAGCUUCUCCUGCCAGGCAGGAAGACGAGUAGAAGGGAGCAGCACCGACGCAUGCUGGAGGCUGGAGCCUGAGCCCCUGGGGCUCGCCUUGCUGUGUUUGGUGGUGACGUGGGACACUGCAGCUCGGCCAGAGUGGUAGAAAUGUCCUGGUGUAGGCUUUUCUGGCUUUGCCGGUCUAGCUGCUCCAAGCCAGGCUGGAGGAGGAGGAGAAGGAAUCACCUGUGGUACGCUGGAGCCUGCAUGUGGCGUGACUCUGCAGCUCGCCUCGUGUGACUGAUGGCAGCCACGGAGACUGCAGCUCGACAGGAGUGAGGCUUCUCAGUGGCUUGAAAGCUCAGCUGACUCCCACGAAGUUUGCCGGAACUCAAGGCUGUCAGUGACAUUCGUGGCGCCAAGACUUAAGCAGGCGCGUUGCAUGCAUCGGCCAGUGUCUGUGCCACGUGCCCUGACGCCACCUGAGAUAAGCACGCCGCACGCCGCACGCCGCACGCGCACGCCGCACGCGCACGCGCACGCCCGGCAGCAGCUUGCUGGCUUGUAACGGCUUGCACGCGCACGCCGCACGCGCAUAACGGUUUGGCCGGCCUGUAACGGCUUGCACGCGCACGCCGCACGCGCGUAACGGCUUGGCUGGCCUGUAAUGGCUUGCACGCGCAUGCUGCACGCGCUUUAACGGCUUGGCUGGCCUGUAGCGGCUUGGCUUGGCUUUGCGUUCUUGGCUUGGCUUGGCGUUGGUAGCUUGGAUUGACGUUUCCUGCUUGGAUUGACGUUUUCUCUCUCGUGUUCCUUUGCUGGGCUUGACCUUUUCUCUGCUGGGUUUGGCAUUCCCUUGGGUGGGCUGGGUGUUUUCUUGGGGGCGGGGGUUGGCCCUUUCUGGGGUUGGCCCUUUCUGGGGUGGGCGUGGGGUCGCCCAGGGGGGGCGUGGGCUUUCCUCGGGUGGGUGUGGGUUUUCCCUGGGUGGGGUGGGCUGGGCUGGAAUCCCCUGCUGGGGUUGGCAGGUUUUGGCUGGGAUUGACAUUUCUCUUCAAACAGAUUGGAAACCCGGAGUUACCUGCUAGUUGGUGAAACUGGUUGGUAGACGCGAUCUGUUGGCUACUACUGGCUUCUCCUGGCUGUUAAAAGCAGAUGGUGGUUGAGGUUGAUUCCAUGCCGGCUGCCUCUUCUGUGAAGAAGCCAUUUGGUCUCAGGAGCAAGAUGGGCAAGUGGUGCUGCCGUUGCUUCCCCUGCUACAGGGAGAGCGGCAAGAGCAACGUGGGCACUUCUGGAGACCACGACGACUCUGCUAUGAAGACACUCAGGAGCAAGAUGGGCAAGUGGUGCCACCACUGCUUCCCCUGCUGCAGGGGGAGUGGCAAGAGCAACGUGGGCGCUUCUGGAGACCACGACGACUCUGCUAUGAAGACACUCAGGAACAAGAUGGGGAAGUGGUGCUGCCACUGCUUCCCCUGCUGCAGGGGGAGCGGCAAGAGCAAGGUGGGCGCUUGGGGAGACUACGAUGACAGCGCCUUCAUGGAGCCCAGGUACCACGUCCGUGGAGAAGAUCUGGACAAGCUCCACAGAGCUGCCUGGUGGGGUAAAGUCCCCAGAAAGGAUCUCAUCGUCAUGCUCAGGGACACUGACGUGAACAAGAAGGACAAGCAAAAGAGGACUGCUCUACAUCUGGCCUCUGCCAAUGGGAAUUCAGAAGUAGUAAAACUCCUGCUGGACAGACGAUGUCAACUUAAUGUCCUUGACAACAAAAAGAGGACAGCUCUGAUAAAGGCCGUACAAUGCCAGGAAGAUGAAUGUGCGUUAAUGUUGCUGGAACAUGGCACUGAUCCAAAUAUUCCAGAUGAGUAUGGAAAUACCACUCUGCACUACGCUAUCUAUAAUGAAGAUAAAUUAAUGGCCAAAGCACUGCUCUUAUAUGGUGCUGAUAUCGAAUCAAAAAACAAGCAUGGCCUCACACCACUGUUACUUGGUGUACAUGAGCAAAAACAGCAAGUCGUGAAAUUUUUAAUCAAGAAAAAAGCGAAUUUAAAUGCACUGGAUAGAUAUGGAAGGACUGCUCUCAUACUUGCUGUAUGUUGUGGAUCAGCAAGUAUAGUCAGCCUUCUACUUGAGCAAAAUAUUGAUGUAUCUUCUCAAGAUCUAUCUGGACAGACGGCCAGAGAGUAUGCUGUUUCUAGUCAUCAUCAUGUAAUUUGCCAGUUACUUUCUGACUACAAAGAAAAACAGAUGCUAAAAAUCUCUUCUGAAAACAGCAAUCCAGAACAAGAGUUAAAGCUGACAUCAGAGGAAGAGUCACAAAGGUUCAAAGGCAGUGAAAAUAGCCAGCCAGAGAAAAUGUCUCAAGAACUAGAAAUAAAUAAGGAUGGUGAUAGAGAGGUUGAAGAAGAAAUGAAGAAGCAUGAAAGUAAUAAUGUGGGAUUACUAGAAAACCUGACUAAUGGUGUCACUGCUGGCAAUGGUGAUAAUGGAUUAAUUCCUCAAAGGAAGAGCAGAACACCUGAAAAUCAGCAAUUUCCUGACAACGAAAGUGAAGAGUAUCACAGAAUUUGUGAAUUACUUUCUGACUACAAAGAAAAGCAGAUGCCAAAAUACUCUUCUGAAAACAGCAACCCAGAACAAGACUUAAAGCUGACAUCAGAGGAAGAGUCACAAAGGCUUAAAGGCAGUGAAAAUGGCCAGCCAGAGAAAAGAUCUCAAGAACCAGAAAUAAAUAAGGAUGGUGAUAGAGAGCUAGAAAAUUUUAUGGCUAUCGAAGAAAUGAAGAAGCACGGAAGUACUCAUGUCGGAUUCCCAGAAAACCUGACUAAUGGUGCCACUGCUGGCAAUGGUGAUGAUGGAUUAAUUCCUCCAAGGAAGAGCAGAACACCUGAAAGCCAGCAAUUUCCUGACACUGAGAAUGAAGAGUAUCACAGUGACGAACAAAAUGAUACUCAGAAGCAAUUUUGUGAAGAACAGAACACUGGAAUAUUACACGAUGAGAUUCUGAUUCAUGAAGAAAAGCAGAUAGAAGUGGUUGAAAAAAUGAAUUCUGAGCUUUCUCUUAGUUGUAAGAAAGAAAAAGACGUCUUGCAUGAAAAUAGUACGUUGCGGGAAGAAAUUGCCAUGCUAAGACUGGAGCUAGACACAAUGAAACAUCAGAGCCAGCUAAGAGAAAAGAAAUAUUUGGAGGAUAUUGAAAGUGUGAAAAAAAAGAAUGAUAAUCUUUUAAAGGCUCUACAAUUGAAUGAGCUCACCAUGGAUGAUGAUACCGCCGUGCUCGUCAUUGACAACGGCUCUGGCAUGUGCAAGGCCGGCUUUGCGGGCGACGAUGCCCCCCGGGCUGUCUUCCCUUCCAUCGUGGGGCGCCCCAGGCAGCAGGGCAUGAUGGGGGGCAUGCAUCAGAAAGAGUCCUAUGUGGGCAAGGAGGCCCAGAGCAAGAGAGGCAUCCUGACCCUGAAGUACCCCAUGGAACACGGCAUCAUCACCAACUGGGAUGACAUGGAGAAGAUCUGGCACCACACCUUCUACAACGAGCUGCGUGUGGCUCCCGAGGAGCACCCCAUCCUGCUGACCGAGGCCCCCCUGAACCCCAAGGCCAACCGCGAGAAGAUGACCCAGAUCAUGUUUGAGACCUUCAACACCCCAGCCAUGUACGUGGCCAUCCAGGCCGUGCCGUCCCUGUACACCUCUGGCCGUACUACUGGCAUCGUGAUGGACUCUGGUGACGGGGUCACCCACACUGUGCCCAUCUAUGAGGGGAAUGCCCUCCCCCAUGCCACCCUGCGCCUAGACCUGGCUGGGCGGGAACUGCCUGACUACCUCAUGAAGAUCCUCACCGAGCGUGGCUAUAGGUUCACCACCAUGGCCGAGCGGGAAAUCGUGCGUGACAUCAAAGAGAAGCUGUGCUAUGUUGCCCUGGACUUCGAGCAGGAGAUGGCCACGGCGGCCUCCAGCUCCUCCCUAGAGAAGAGCUACGAGCUGCCCGAUGGCCAGGUCAUCACCAUCGGCAACGAGCGGUUCCGCUGCCCCGAGGCGCUCUUCCAGCCUUGCUUCCUGGGCAUGGAAUCCUGUGGCAUCCAUGAAACUACCUUCAACUCCAUCAUGAAGUCUGAUGUGGACAUCCGCAAAGACCUGUACACCAACACAGUGCUGUCUGGCGGCACCACCAUGUACCCUGGCAUGGCCCACAGAAUGCAGAAGGAGAUCGCUGCCCUGGCGCCUAGCAUGAUGAAGAUCAGGAUCAUUGCUCCUCCCAAGCGCAAGUACUCCGUGUGGGUCGGUGGCUCCAUCCUGGCCUCGCUGUCCACCUUCCAGCAGAUGUGGAUCAGCAAGCAGGAGUAUGAUGAGUCAGGCCCCUCCAUUGUCCACCGCAAAUGCUUCUAGGUGGACUCUGACUUAGUUGCGUUACACCCUUUCUUGACAAAACCAAACUUCUCAGAAAACAACAUGAGAUUGGCAUGGCUUUAUUUGUUUUCUUGUUUCAUUUUUUGUUUUGUUUUUUAUUGGCUUGACUCAGGAUUUAAAAACCGGAAUGGUGAAGGUGACAGCAGUCGGUUGGAGGAAGCUUCCUCCAAAGUUCUACAAUGUUGCCAAGGACUUUGAUUGUACAUUGUUCUUCUUUUCAAUAGUCAUUCCAAAUAUUGUGAGACGCAUUGUUUCAGGAAGCCCCUUGCCCUGCUAAAAGCCAUCCCACUUCUCUCUAAGGAGAAUGGCCCAGUCCUCUCCCUAGUUCACACAGGGGAGGUGAUAGCAUUGCUUUUGUGCAAAUUACAUAAUGCAAAAUUUUUUGAAUCUUCGCCUUAAUACUUUUUAAUUUUGUUUUAUUUUGAAUGAUCAGCCUUCGUGGCCCCCCUCUUUUGUACCCCAACUUGGGGUGUAUGAAGGCUUUUGGUCUCCCUGAGAGUGGCUGGAGGCAGCCAGGGCUUACCUGUACUCUGACUUGAGGAGAGUUGGA